ACCCCUAAAGACGCUAGCGCUGCGAUGGCGGAGGCCGUGGAGCGCACUGACGAGCUGGUCCGGGAGUACCUGCUCUUCCGCGGGUUCACGCACACACUGCGGCAGCUGGACGCCGAGAUCAAGGCGGACAAGGAGAAGGGGUUCCGGGUGGAUAAGAUUGUGGACCAGCUGCAGCAGUUAAUGCAGGUGUAUGACUUGGCUGCCCUUCGGGAUUAUUGGAGCUACUUGGAGCGUCGGCUCUUCAGCCGCUUGGAGGAUAUAUACAGACCCACAAUCCACAAGCUGAAAACCAGCCUGUUUCGAUUUUAUCUUGUCUACACAAUCCAGACAAACAGAAAUGACAAGGCUCAGGAGUUCUUUGCAAAGCAGGCCACGGAACUCCAGAACCAGGCUGAGUGGAAGGAUUGGUUUGUCCUGCCCUUCCUGCCAUCCCCGGACACCAACCCCACCUUUGCUACCUACUUUUCUCGACAGUGGGCUGACACCUUCAUUGUGUCCCUGCACAACUUCCUGAGCGUCCUGUUUCAGUGCAUGCCAGUCCCUGUGAUCCUGAACUUUGAUGCGGAGUGUCAGAGGACUAACCAGGUUCAAGAAGAAAAUGAAGUUCUGCGUCAGAAGCUUUUUGCAUUGCAAGCUGAAAUCCACCGACUGAAGAAAGAGGAGCAACAGCCAGAAGAGGAAGAGGCCUUGGUCCAACACAAAUUGCCUCCUUAUGUCUCCAACAUGGACCGCCUGGGGGACUCGGAACUUGCCAUGGUGUGCAGCCAAAGGAAUGCCUCCCUCUCCCAGUCACCUCGUGUGGGCUUCCUGUCCUCGCUGCUGCCUCAGAGUAAGAAGAGCCCCUCAAGGUUGUCGCCUGCUCAGGGCCCUCCUCAACCUCAGAGCUCGGCCAAGAAAGAGUCCUUCGGUGGUCAGGGCACCAAGGGAAAGGACCCGACGUCCGGAGCCAAGGAUGGGAAGAGCCUCCUCAGCGGGCUGGCCACUGGGGAGUCCGGUUGGUCACAGCACCGGCAGCGGCGCCUGCAGGACCAUGGCAAGGAGAGGAAGGAGCUUUUCUCCACAACCACUUCCCAGUGUGCAGAGAAGAAACCAGAAGCCAGUGGCCCAGAGGCUGAGCCCUGCCCAGAGCUCCACACGGAGCCAGUGGAGCCACUGACUCGGGCAUCCUCGGCAGGCCCUGAGGGUGGAGGAGUCCGCCCCGAGCAGCCCUUUAUUGUGCUGGGACAGGAGGAGUACGGGGAACACCACUCAUCCAUCAUGCACUGCAGAGUGGACUGCUCUGGGAGGAGAGUCGCCAGCUUAGACGUAGAUGGGGUCAUCAAAGUGUGGUCCUUCAACCCCAUCAUGCAGACCAAAGCAUCCUCCAUUUCCAAAUCACCGCUGCUGUCUUUGGAAUGGGCCACCAAACGGGACAGACUGCUCUUGCUGGGCAGUGGUGUGGGAACAGUGCGUCUCUAUGACACGGAAGCCAAGAAGAAUCUCUGUGAAAUCAAUAUCAACGACAACAUGCCCAGGAUCCAGCCUCAGGACCAAAGUGCACCCUCCCUCUGUGGGCAGGCAGAGGGUCUGACCCAGGCCCAUGUGUGUUGCAGAAUCCUGUCUCUUGCGUGCAGCCCCAACGGGGCCUCUUUCGUCUGUUCGGCAGCAGCUCCGAGCCUCACUUCCCAGGUGGACUUCUCAGCACCAGACAUCGGCAGCAAGGGCAUGAACCAGGUUCCUGGCAGGCUGCUGCUGUGGGACACGAAAACCAUGAAGCAGCAGCUCCAGUUCUCCCUGGAUCCAGAACCCAUUGCUAUCAACUGUACAGCCUUCAAUCACAACGGGAACCUGCUGGUCACAGGGGCAGCUGAUGGCGUCAUCCGGCUGUUUGACAUGCAGCAGCAUGAGUGCGCGAUGAGCUGGAGGGCCCACUACGGGGAGGUCUACUCUGUGGAGUUCAGCUAUGAUGAGAACACCGUGUACAGCAUCGGCGAGGACGGGAAGUUCAUCCAGUGGAACAUCCACAAGAGUGGCCUCAAGGUAUCCGAGUACAGCCUCCCCUCAGAUGCCACGGGCCCCUUUGUGCUGUCUGGAUACAGCGGCUACAAGCAGGUUCAAGUCCCCAGGGGCCGACUCUUCGCUUUUGACUCGGAGGGAAAUUACAUGCUGACAUGUUCUGCCACAGGCGGCGUCAUCUACAAGCUGGGUGGCGAUGAGAAGGUUCUGGAGAGCUGCUUGAGCCUAGGUGGCCACCGAGCCCCUGUGGUCACCGUGGACUGGAGCACUGCCAUGGACUGUGGGACCUGCCUCACCGCCUCCAUGGAUGGCAAGAUCAAGCUGACCACCCUCCUGGCCCAUAAAGCCUGAUGACUUGCCCCAAGGGCCACCCGAGGAAGCAGUAUUAUCUGCGGUGGGGGGAGGAGAUAUAGGACAGGAAAACCACGUGCUCCACUCCAGCUCCCUGCCAGUGCAGUGACUCUGCAGGGAAAGACUGGCAAGGAGGCUCAGGUGCUUCCAUCUGUGGUGACUGGAAUGGGACCCACGUGGAGUAGGUGACAUAUGCUUCCCAGAGACUGGUAUUGUGGCUGUGCCAGGAGUACAUGUGAGACUAUGGGAGGAAAGCUCCGGAAGAAGGAGAAACAUUGCAGUGGCUACUGUGUUGGCCCAGUAGAAAUUGACAGUAUUUUGUAUAUAUGUGCCCAUUUAUCUUUUUCUUUUUUAAAAAAAGAGAAUACUCUUGUGGUCCCCUGAUGUCUCUUUCUAGGAUGUGUGUCACUUUGCUUCAGUGACAGCCCUCCCACCCAGCCUGGCUCUGCUGGCCCUGAACUGAACCUCUCCAGGCUCUCCUGUUGCUUUGCCAUGGAGCCAGGUCAGCUCUCUGUCUGUUCUGCUGGGUAACAAGGUUUGGCAGUUCCUGUUUCUCUGGGCUUAAGUCAAGGCCACAGAAUUCUUUUUCUUCCCUGAAAGCUGGCAGCUUUUGUUACAGAAGAUUCUCAGGAUGAAGGCAGGGGCUGAGGCCUCUGCUACUGGCUGCCCCUUUCCAUCCAGUGGCUGCUGUUUCCCAAGACAGGCUAAGCGUUUCUUAUCUGAAAUGCUUGGGACAGGAGUGUUACAGAUUUUGGAUUUUUUCAGACUUUGGAAUAUUUGCAUAUAUACAUAAUGAGGUAUCUUGGUAGGUCUCAUGUCUAAACAUGAAAUUCAUUCAUGUUUUAUAUAUACCUUAUACAUGUAGCCUGAAGGUAACUCUAUACAGUAUUUUAAAUAAUUUUGUACAUGAAACAAAGUAUUGAUUGUGGUCAGGUGUGGUAUUUUCCACUUGUGGUGUCAUGUUGGUGCUCACAGUUUUGGGGCUGGGCACGGUGGCUCACGUCUGUAAUCCCAGCACUUUGGGAGGCCAAGGUGGGUGGAUCACUUAAGGUCAGGAGCUUGAGACCAGCCUGGCCAACAUGGUGAAACCCCAUCUCUACUAAAAAUACCAAAAUUAGCCAGGCAUGGUGGCAGGUGCCUAUAAUCCCAGCUACUCUGGAGGCUGGGGCAGGAGAAUCACUUGAGCCCAGGAGGCGGAGGUUGCAGUGAGCCGAGAUCACGCCACUGGGAGAACCCAACUCAAAAAAAAAAAAAGUUUUGGGUUAUGGAGCAUUUUUGAUUUUGGAUCUUUGGGUUAAGGACGCUCAACCUGUACCUUUUUCAUUUGGUGGCUCCUCUCAUUCCUCCAACUGAACAUCUUUGUGGAAAGAUGAUGGCUGCCUGCACCCACUGCUGGCGAAUGGUGAGAAGGUAGAGCAAGGGGGCCAAGUUGCUGCUGGUGGGCACCUGGGGUUCAGGCCGGCCCAACUGUGGCUGAGCCGAUCUGUAGCUGAGCUGAGUGUCAACCAGCUGUGUCCACACCCUGCCUGAGGCCUGCCCUCUCCUCCCUGGCUGGGGUGGGACCUUGAAGAGGCAUAUCUUCCCACUAGGUGAGGAGGAACAAGAGCCUCACUCCCCUUCUCCCUCUUGCCUUUCACAGCUGAGGCAGAGCUUAUGGGAGGAGUCACUAUGGGAGUGAUGGACCUGGGCUUUGGUCUCCAGUGUUUGGCAGGGGCGACCUUAUCACUGAGCUGGGGAAGGCAGCUGCCAUGAGUCAUUUUAAGUCUCUGAGCUCCAGCCCAGUUCUAGGGGCACAAGGCUGGAGUAGGGAUACUCCUAGUUACCUGCUUGAGGAAAAGCACGAAGAAAUUGGUACCAAAGUCUUGGCUUUGUUCUGGGAGUUGAGGGAAAAGUAGGGAGGUAUUUAAGUGGCUUGAUUAUGAGAAAACACCAGAGACAGUAGUAAAUAGUUAUUUACCGAUUUUUACCCAUUUCUACCCUGGUAAUCCUCCCUGCAAAUGAAGAAAACCAAGACUUCUUUAUUUAUUAUCUUUCCCCAUCUGUAUUGAAACAGUGAUCUUACUUAUCUCACCCAGUGAUUCUGUAGGACAUUUAAAAAGUGGUCAUGGGUUUCAUUGGAGUGAGAAUGGUAUUAACGUUUCCUCUUGUCAUCUCAAAGUUUUCUCUCCCCUUAAUACCAUCUCUACAGCUUGCUGAGAUGCUUUAAGGAUCACAGAGACACAAAGAAAAUUUGAACCCUACGCUUCUCCCAUCCCACUUCUUACUCCAUCCCGGGUGAGCGCUCGUCCUCAAAUAAAGCAUGUUGGAACUUC